AGUCAGUCGCUCCCUGUCGCUGCCGGAGAGUCUCUGCUUCCCCCUUCCUACGCGCUCCGCGGCGGUAGCUCGGGCUCUCCGGAGGAGGGGGCGACAGAGUAAAAGAGAGGCUGACUUAAUAAAGUUUCCUGAAACAACAACUACCACCGAAAAGGCCCAAGGUUGGGGGAGACCCCCAUUUUUCUCCGCCCCUCUCCUAAAGCCUGAGGGACCGUUGCAGGUGGAGCGGCGCUGGUGGGACCCGGGUUGCGGCGGCAGCCGUUGCCCCGGCGAGGGAAGCCUCAGGUCCUGCCCGCUCCGGUUCCGGCUCCUUCGGUGGUGGCGGCGGCAGCUGCUGCCGGGCGGUUCCUCCUGUCAACUGCCUCCGCCCGCGCGCCUCCCGCCUAGCCACACAGCGCGGAGGACGCCGUGAGCCGCCGCCGCAGUCGUCUCGGCCCGCGGAGGGACGUGGUGAGCUGUGGCGCUUCCGCGUCAGCGCCGGCGGGGACUCUUUGGGAGCGCGUCGGGCCCGAGUCCGGGUUCCCCCGCGUGGUCAGCGGAGGCUGCGCCAGGUGGGGCCCGCAGCCGCCUCCCACGCCAGGCUGUCCCCGCGGCCGCCCGGCCUGCCUUCCUUCCUUCCGCCCGCCCGCCGGCCCGCCCUAAGAGUUGAGUAAGUUGGGCGCACUUGGUUGUGGGGACGGGGUCUCCGCCAGGGAGACCCCAACGCACGUGCGUAGCGGGAGGGCGCGGCGUGGGCCAGCAGCCGGCGGGAGCGGCACCUCCGUAGUCCCGGAGCCCGGCGGUGCCCGCCGCGCUCUGCGCUCCGUUUCCGCGCGCCCGCCCGGGACGGCGAGGCCGCAGCCGCCCGCGCUGCCGGCCAGGCCUUCGCCCUGCGCUGCGCACCCGAGGCUGCGUUUCCGGCCACGCCGCAAUGAAGAGCUUCUUACAGUGAAAGCAAAGUAGGUCGAGUCCACUGAAAAUGCCUUUAAGGGACAAAUACUGUCAGACUGACCACCAUCAUCACGGAUGCUGUGAACCAGGAACUAAACAACUUAAGCAUAUUUUAUUAAAAGAUGUGGACACUAUUUUUGAAUGUAAGUUAUGCCGCAGUCUCUUCAGAGGAUUACCAAAUUUAAUUACCCAUAAAAAAUUCUACUGCCCACCAAGUCUCCAGAUGGAUGACAACCUUCCUGAUGUAAAUGAUAAACAAAGCCAAGCCAUAAAUGAUCUCCUAGAAGCCAUAUAUCCAAGUGUGGACAAACGAGAAUAUAUUAUUAAGCUAGAACCCAUAGAAACUAAUCAAAAUGCAGUAUUUCAAUAUAUUUCGAGGACUGAUAAUCCUAUUGAAGUCACAGAGUCAAGCAGUACUCCUGAACAAACCGAAGUUCAGAUACAGGAAACUAGCACUGAACAGUCAAAAACAGUACCGGUUACAGAUACAGAGGUGGAAACUGUAGAGCCCCCUCCUGUUGAGAUUGUUACAGAUGAAGUUGCACCUACAUCUGAUGAACAACCUCAGGAGUCGCAGGCUGACUUGGAAACUUCUGACAAUUCUGAUUUUGGUCACCAGUUGAUAUGUUGUCUUUGUAGAAAAGAAUUCAAUUCUAGACGAGGUGUUCGCCGUCACAUUCGAAAAGUACACAAGAAAAAGAUGGAAGAACUAAAAAAGUACAUUGAAACACGAAAGAAUCCAAACCAAUCCUCUAAAGGACGCAGUAAGAAUGUUCUAGUUCCAUUAAGUAGGAGUUGUCCAGUAUGUUGUAAAUCAUUUGCUACAAAAGCGAAUGUAAGGAGGCAUUUUGAUGAAGUUCAUAGAGGACUAAGGAGGGAUUCAAUUACUCCUGAUAUAGCAACAAAGCCUGGGCAACCUUUGUUCCUGGAUUCUAUUUCUCCUAAAAAAUCUUUUAAGACUCGAAAACAAAAGUCUUCUUCAAAGGCUGAAUACAAUUUAACUGCAUGCAAAUGCCUCCUUUGCAAGAGGAAAUAUAGUUCACAAAUAAUGCUUAAAAGACAUAUGCAAAUUGUCCACAAGAUAACUCUUUCUGGAACAAACUCUAAAAGAGAAAAAGGCCCUAAUAAUACUGCCAACAGUUCAGAAAUAAAAGUUAAAGUUGAACCAGCAGAUUCUGUAGAAUCUUCACCCCCUUCCAUUACCCAUUCUCCACAGAAUGAAUUAAAGGGAACAAAUCAUUCAAAUGAAAAAAAGAACACACCGGCAGCACAGAAAAAUAAAGUUAAACAAGACUCUGAAAGCCCUAAAUCAACUAGUCCGUCGGCUGCAGGUGGCCAGCAAAAAACCAGAAAACCAAAACUUUCAGCUGGCUUUGACUUUAAGCAACUUUACUGUAAACUUUGUAAACGUCAGUUUACUUCCAAACAGAACUUGACUAAACACAUCGAGUUGCACACAGAUGGAAAUAACAUUUAUGUUAAAUUCUACAAGUGUCCUCUUUGCACUUAUGAAACUCGUCGGAAACGUGAUGUGAUACGACAUAUAACUGUGGUUCAUAAAAAGUCAUCUCGUUAUCUUGGGAAAAUAACAGCCAGUUUAGAGAUCAGAGCUAUAAAAAAGCCUAUUGAUUUUGUUCUAAAUAAAGUGGCAAAAAGAGGCCCUUCGAGGGAUGAAGCAAAACAUAGUGAUUCAAAACAUGAUGGCACUUCUAACUCUCCUAGUAAAAAGUAUGAAGUAGCUGACGUCGGUAUUGAAGUAAAAGUCACAAAAAACUUUUCUCUUCACAGAUGCAAUAAAUGUGGAAAGGCAUUUGCCAAAAAGACUUACCUUGAACAUCAUAAGAAAACUCAUAAGGCAAAUGCUUCCAAUUCACCUGAAGGAAACAAAACCAAAGGCCGAAGUACAAGAUCUAAGGCUCUUGUCUGGUGAGGAACAGUUAACAGAGUUUUGCUUUUUUCCCCCCAUCGAACUAAAAAAAAAAUCAUUUGACCAUAAUUUAUAGCUGGUUCCAUUUUAACACGUUUGCUUCCAUAUAUCUCAUGGCAAUGGGAACUGCAAGAGUAAUGUGCAUAUUGCAUUUACCUCUUCAGUGACCUUUAUUCCAGUGGCUUGGGAACAAAAGUUAACUUCAGAACUUAUCUUCCACAGGACAAUGCAAUGUAGUUGUAGGUAGAUGGCACAGGGUCAGUGCUUUCCUUUUAAUGUUGUAAAAUAUAUACAUUUAUAUUGGCUUAUGUUUACAAUAGAAGUCUUCUGUUUAACUAACUUUGCACAGGUUUAAUUUGAUUCAGUGACUUAGUCUACUAAUUAAUGAAUUGUAGGAAAGUUAAAUAUAUUAGAAUGAACUUGUGAAGGCGAUAACUAUAGGAAAAAAUCUUUUGAGGCACUGUAAUUAUUGUAAAAAUUAAUCUGUGACGGCUAAAUAAAAUGCUGCACUCAGAAAAAAAAAUCCCCGAAUUGAAUUAAAAAUGAUUAGCAUUUAUCAUUUACUUUUAACAUAGUGCUUCCAGGCAAAGGGGGAAAGUUGGUGGUAAAUAGAAGUUUGGAUUUUUUUUCCUUCUCCUUGGGAGUGUGUGUUAGUUACUGUUUUUUAGUUUUGAUCUAUGGAAACAAUGCUUAUUUAGGUCCCAAAUGCUUCCCCUCUCUUUUUAAUAAACUUUUUGGUGAUCAUUUUAACAUAGUUAAUAUUAUUAACUAGGGAUUUGUUUUUUGUGGUUGUGUGUCGUAAGAAAAGUAAAAUUCAUAUUUGGAAGAAAGAAAAAUACUACUUUUUUUUUUUUUUUUUUGAGACGGAGUUUCGCUCUUGUUGCCCAGGCUGGAGUGCAGUGGUGCAAUCUCGGCUCACUACACCUUCCGCCUCCUGGGUUCAAGCAAUUCUCCUGCCUCAGCCUCCCAAGUAGCUGGGAUUACAGGCAUAAGCCACCACACCCGGCUAAUUUUGUAUUUUUAGUAGAGAUGGGGUUUCAUCAUGUUGGUCAGGCUGGUCUCAAAACUCCUGGACCUCAGGUGAUCCGCCCACCUCGGCCUCCCAAAGUGCUGGGGUUACAGGCAUGAGCCACCGUGCCUGGCCAAAAAAUACUACUUGUUAAAGAAGGUUUUGGAACAAAUGUAGAUUUUUAAAAAAUGCAACAUAAAAUGAGUAGACUCCCUAUACUUUUCGCAAGUCUAUAUAUAUUUUAAAAGUUCACCUUCUAUACCUGUGUCCCCUGUAUUAAGGCAUUUAAUGUAUUUAAUGAGUAUUAAAUUAGUUUCAGAUUCAGGUUCUAAAGCAAAAUAUUAGUUUGAGUGCUGUGAGGGUUAAAUGUUGUGGUUUGAUUAUCACACGUUUUUUUAUUUGUGUGGAAAACUUGAGAUGAAACCAUCUUUUAGAAGUAAUUUACUGUUGCAUAGUUUUAAAAACUAGGUUUUAUUAGUAAACUCAAAAGUGUUCAUUUAUUCCCAUUUCUCCUCAGAUAACUUCAAGUGAUGUACGAAAAGGUUUGGAGUUCAUUUUUGUGGAAAGACUUUAAAUUGGUGUUAGAACCACUAAACAUCUUCAAAUGGUACUAUGAGGAAAAAAAGAAAAACAUUUUUCUAAAUAUUCAACUAUAACUGCUGUUUUCUGACUAAAAUAACCAUCUAACCACUUGUUUCUAAGGCACUGCCUAUUCCAGCACUUUCAAGUAGCUGUGAUAUUACAUGUUGUCAUCACAGUCCAUCAGCUAUCCACCCUUGACCUUGUGCAUUUGGUCGACAGUUUCUACAAAAAUGUUACAAAUUUUGUUUUCUAAACAAUUUGUUGAUUAAGUGAUCAACAACCUGAAGAAAAUAUCAAUUUUUAAUUGACAAAGACUUUAUAUCUUAGUGAUUUUAGUUUUGUUUCUCUUUAUUUGGCAACAUUUUCAUCUGAAUUGUAUAGAUAUAUGAUUUUCUAGUGAGUGUAUGUUAGGAACAAAAGACAAAAUAGUAUCAACACAUUAUAAAUAUUUAGCUUACUAAAUAUUUGUAAUUAUUUUUACAUCCAUUUAUUUCUAGCUUGUUCUCCAGCACUUCAGUGUUUGAAAGUUUCAUCCUAAAAUAUAUACUACAGGAAAGCUGCAGUUCAUUUUCAUGCAUGGAUCAUUACAUUUUUCACUUGUAAAUGUAGGUUUUUAUGAAAAUUAAACAUUCCCCUAUUUUUCUUUAAAUUUUAUACAAAGCACUUUAAUGAUAGAUGCAACCUUAUUUUUCAGUUCCUAUUUUUUUAAAGACCACACAUUUACUAAUGUUAAUAUGAAGGUAAUAAAUAGCUUACUGAUAUUUUAUGGAUGCAGACAAUCCAUGCACAACCACUUCUUAUGAUACUAGUUUAUUUCCUUAAAUAUUGCUACAAAAGGAAGAUGCGGGUGUAAGCCCUGAUUUUUUUUUCUCCCAAGAAAAAUCUUAAAGGACCACUUUAGAUAAUAUUUGAUUCCUACUGUAAAAUUUAGAAAAUGAUGAAUUCUUGUCCAUUUUUGUAAUCAAGAUUUUAGGAAAAACAGAAGUACAUCUAUCUUUAUGAAAUUUUGGGCAGGUUUUUGUGUAUCAAUAUUUUGUACUUUUAGGGAAUAUUUUAUUUUUUAGUUAUUUGUGUCAAAUUAUAAUUAUAAAAGGUACAGCAGAAAAUAUACCAUGUUUUUAUAUAGGUUCACACCUGUACUUAGGAGGGACCCUGUCCAUCUAUAUACUUUUUGUAUAAAAUUUUAAAAUGUUAAAGAUCCACAAGGUCUUAAUAAAAUGAUUCUAUAGCUAGAAAAACAUUUACCUUCCCAGUGCUUUGCACUAAAAUAUACUGUGAAAGGAAACUAGAAAGACUGUAACUAUUGCUGGAAAUGUUCUAUAUUGAAUGUACAUGCUCUUGUUGGAAAAAUGUACUAUAUGUGAUGGAAAUAAACCAGAAUCGAAGUUAUUUCAGCUAAAUGUGCUUCAGCAAAGGUGCAUUGGUUGAAACUUAAAUGUUUUAUUAUCAAAUUUAAACUUAUUCAGUGACUAUGAGCAGCUACACUUGAAUUAUAUUCUGAUAGUUUUAUUUCUAAGAAAUAGAGUAAUAAUUUCUCUUUAAUUUAAAAACAGAUUUACUUUCCCACAUAUUGAAAAUUUGUACUUAUAGAUCUAACUUUAAUAACUAAUAGUAUAAUAUAUUUAGGGAACUAAAUGUGUAGGUGGUAUUUCAUUUAUAAGCCAUCUUCAUUAGUUGCACAUUAUUAAACCUAUAUGUUUGACUUUUGCAAGGUGUUAUCUUUUAUGCAUUCCUACACACAAGACAUAUUCCAAAGAUAUUUUCCAGAUAAAUGCUGAUAACCCCUGAAAAGAUAUGAGGAUUCCUAAAAAGCUAGGGGUUGCUCUUUGCAGCAUCCUCUCAUUUGUAUGCCAGCCUUUCCCUCUCUGCUUGCUUGUUAAAUACUAUAGAGAAGAAAGAAAAAUUGAUAUUGGAGGAGGGGAGCCCAUUGCUGGAAUUCUCUUACUCUACCCACCUAUUUCUACAGGACCAUUCACAGUGUGUCUCCUCCAUAGUAAUUCUGGGGCCACAGAAUAGGAAUCUAGAGGAGGAAAUAAAUGAGAGUUCCAGGGCUGUCAAAAGAUUUCAUCUGGGUCAUGUAGGAAAAAUAGCACUGUGUCAGUACUUGCCUACAUUAGACAGACUGGAAACAUUUUAUCAUAAUAGCUGAAUUAAUGGAUAAUGGCAUAUAUAAGAGAACCUGAACUAGGACCAGUUUAGAAAGGUAGAACAAACAAGUGACCACAAAGUAUUGUUCUUCUUAUUCCUUUCUGGUCUUCAUCCUUCCUGAUUUGACUUGAGCUCUGUCACUUCAGGGGCUCAGGCUUAAGGCUCUUGAGAAGAGGCCUAAGAAGUUUGUGCCAGAAGCUUUUCUGCAUGUAGGCUACAUAAACACAUAUUUAGGUGAUUUUGUAUUGUUAUAGUGAGGAUUACAGCACACAAAGAGCCAUCAGAAACUGCUUAUUUUAUAUAAGACCUAUCUGGCUAUAAAUUAUAUCUACCUUUGCUGCUAUUUGAUCAAUUAAGAGUUUUCCUAUGGAAUUCAACUUACCUUCCUUCCUAAAGAUGCCUUCCAUUCCUAAGUGUGGUGGGAGAGGAGAAACAACAGGCGUAGGUUGCUCUUCAACUUUAUAAGUUUGAAUAGUGCAAAUGAGAGCUGAAGUAUAGCUGACAUUGGGCAGGUGUUCAUUAGACAUGCCUUGAAUACACAACAACCAUUUCUUUUUUUUUUUGGUUUAUGUCUCCAUUCCCUCCCCCUCCCCUUUACUCUUUAAGAAGAAAACCUUUGAAGAGUGUACACAUUACCCAUUCUUAGGUUUUAGUUUUUUGUCUAGUUUUGUAUAUAUGAAUUAAGUUUUUGGUUGACACAGGUUGCUUUAGUUGUUGAAAUGUACCUUCAGAUUUUUUAGGAAUAUAUUUAUUAUAUUACUUUAUGGUCAAUAAAUAGUCUGUUCUGCUCAGUUUGCAUUAAAGAGCCUAUGGAUGCAGUAGUGGGGAGUUAAUGAUUUUGCUAUGGCAUGAGGCUGUGGGUAUAGAAAGAGGAGUUUCCCUGUAGGUGUUAUGGUAAAUACAUGUGGAGAUAGGUAGAAGUGAUUAUCAUUCCCUGUUGUGAAGUUGCAAAAGAUCUCUUCAAAUAGCAUGACUUCUGAAAAUGAGGUAGAGAUGCUUCAAAAAUUUUGGAAAUUAUGUUUCCAGGUUUCCUGCAGUGACCCAUUGAAGUAUUCUAGAUCCUUAGUUUGGAGUUGGAGAAGUUAUUUUUCUAAUGGAAUCCAUAGAUUAUCAGGAUUAUGAUUUAGCCAUGGCUUUCAGUUGAUCUGAAGCCAAGCUCUAAGAUAUGUGCAGCAGGAUAUUGGCUGUGCUGUUAGACAAAUCCUUCUGUACUCUGUGCUAUCCUGUCGUCUCUCUUUAAGAGCUAAAGGGAUCCUUGGUAUUGAAAAGGAAUAAGGAUCAGCAAUUUCAGGAAUAGCUGUUCUGUGGUUUUUGAGGCAUUAAACACAUGGUAGAAUGCAGAUUAAAAACAUGUCUCACUUAAAACCUACAAUUAUUUUGGCUUUUCUAACUUUCCAAAUUCAUUUCUCUUCUCCUAAAUUGUUUCUAUACCCUAUUCCUCUGAGCUUCCAGCUUCUACCUUGCCUUUUCUUCUUCUAGUUUAAUAGAAAUCAUUAGUACCAAGAUAGCUAAAGUGUUUUUUGGAAGGGUAAGAGUAUGGAAAAUGCAGCUCAUUUCCUCCUAAAUCUUCAUUGCUCCACACCAAAUUUGGGAGGCUUAUUAUUUUCAAGCCUCUUCCUCUACAUAUUUUCACCACUACAACACCACAAACAAAAAGGGACCUAGCAUACCAUAGGUGCAUCUGUUUGAGAAAAUGCCCAAAGUUGGAGGUUUUGGUGUUUGCGUCCACUCAGCAGAAUUAAUUUGCUUGAUUGUGUAUUUUUGAUGUCAGGGACUCUCUUGAUAAUUUUGUACGGUGCCUAGCACAUUUUCAUGUAUACCAAGACACUUCAAAUAAAUAUUUGAUAAUGGUAUUAAGGCAAGUAAGCCUUUUCCAUCUCUAAAUUGUACACCAUGUAUUUUGAGACUUCAAGUCUUAACAUUUUAUCUUCUCAAUAUUGAUGGAUUUCACUUGUUUUUAGGAAAUUUCACCAGUGUUGUGUUUAUAAAAAAGAAAGAUAAUUCUUAGUAAUAGCUAAUAAUAAUGAACAUUUAUGGCAUGCUUGUUAUAUGCCAAGCACUCUGCUAAAUCUUUUCAUGCAUAAUGUCCCUAAUCCUACCAACAACUCUAUGAAGUAAAACCUAUUCUUUCAUUAUCCCUGUUUUAUGGAACAGAAAAUAGAAACUUAGAGAAGUUCAGUGAUUUACUUAGGUUCACAUAGCUGGUAAGAAACUUACACUAGUCAUCUAAUUGGCGUGUAAAUGCAUAUGUACCCAUAGAUACAAAUGUUAUGUUAUGCUCUUUUUUUGAGUUGCAAGCACAGAAUUUUACUUGGUAGCUUCUAAGGAGAGUUUUAUUAGAAGACUUUAUUUGGGGAAAUAUGGGAGAUAUAAGUGAUCAGGCCUUAUAGGAUUCCAAGAGUAAUUGUACAACUCAGCUUCACCAUUCAGAUUUCAACUAGGUAGGUGUUACAAAAUGAGAAAAAAAAAUCAGUGCAACUCUAGUGUCUGGAUGUUGCCCUCUGAGCAGCAGAAGUAUUGCUUCUCUGCUGCUAUUAGCCCUUUUCAGACUCUGCUUUAUUUUGUUUUAAACAAAUUACCUCACUCUGUAUCUUCUCAAUAUGGUCUUAACUGCCUCGUUCCACCCUCUGCUCUGUGUCCUUCCGCUACUUUCCCCUUCUGUACAGCUUGAGUUCAAUCUUCUGUAAGAGGAAAUCUAAUUAGUCCAGUUAGAUUCAUUGCCUGUUGGGCUAAUCUCUCAUGUCAGUCCCCUUCAUAGGUUGCUGGCCAGUCUGUAGAUUGGCUGCUCUUGGGACAGUUGCUCUCUCUUGGUCCUGUCAUUUGUGAUCAUAGUGGCAGAGUCAGUGGCAUAAAACAUGGCCCUGGGCCCCAUAGAAGGAAUCUUUUGGUGGGAAUCUCUUAAAAGACCAUAGUCCUAAAAUGUGAUGAGCUUUCCAGUAUACAUGUUUUUCUUUCUUUUGAAAGGUGACAGAAUGAAAGGCAAGUUGUGAUCUUGACUGUUAGGUCAAUGCAGCAUCAGCAAUCCUUUCCCUACUGAGAAAAUGUGGAAAAUAGUGUUUUGAUCAGUAUCUGCAUUUCCUUUUCUAAACUGCCUGAUGACAUUUCCUUCUUUGGGUUUGUAGAUUCAUAGACAGCCUGAAGUUUUCCCUCAGAAAGAGCCAUUACAUUUUUUGUAGCAGCAUAUUAGGCCACCGCAUCAGUUGCUGCUGUUUUCCAGACAUCCACAAUUAUGCUGCAUAGUUUGAGUUGGUGAUUUAGUGAAUCCUCAAAGUAUUGUUUCUGCUUUUCUGUUUGUGCUUUCCACAUUUGGGCUUACUGUGCAAUGGCUGCUUUAUAUCCUGUCAUUCAUUCCUUCAAUGACAGACACUAUCGAGCAUCCAUCAUGUGCCUAGCAUCAUUCCAUUCUUUUGGGGAAACAGUCAUACAGUGGUUAAAGCACGGAUUUUUUAAGAGUCAAGAAGACCUGAAUUCAAGUCCUGGCUUCUUUGCUUACUAGCUCUGUAGUGUGGGCAAGUUACCAAAUCUUUCUAAGCUUCAAUUUUCCUGUCUGUAAAAUGAUUAUAUUAGAAACUACCUUAUAGGUAGGUUUAUUGUGGGAAUUUAUAAAAGCUUAAUGAUGUGUAUAGUGUACUUAGCACAAUACCUGGCUCAGGGAAGAGCUCAGUAAAUAUUAUUACUGUCGUAGUGAUCACUGAACUUGUAUCGGUUUCUUUCUGAAAUACUUUCUAGCACUUAGCUUUUGGUUAUCUUGCUUUGCCAUUUGAUGUUUGUUGCCUUCUUGUUGGCAAUAAUCCAACCGUUAAAUGAAAAGUCAAAUGUAACAUCUGUGAUAAAGCCAAGAUACACAGAAGUUUAUUAAGUUAGAGCACUUCGUUAUUUUAUGGGCCUUUAUGCUGGAGUUUGGUGCCAUUUUUGGUGGCACCUUUUGCUAAUUGUUCACGAAUUUGCUGACCUUUUAUGAUAUUAUUUUGUUUCUUCAUGAUUAAUGUCUUAUUGAACAAUGUGUAGUUUUGAAUAGCAAAACUCAGGACAGUUUUGUUUUGUUUUGUUUUGGUAAACAUUAGGCUGUGGGUACAGGAAUGUAUUUUGAGAUUACAAGCAAGAAUUGUCUUUUCUUUGUAUCACCAAUGCCUCAUAGUGUACCUAGCACACAACAGUUGCUAAGAGAAUGAUGAAGAAAGAAGGAAGGCAGGAACAACACUUCAGUUAUCUUCAGGCUUAUCUUAUCAUUAGUCAACAGUCUGUCUUGGGUUUUACUUCUUUUCCCAUUACAUGAUCUAAUCUGUAUAGCUUCUCUACAUGUGAGAUUCCUCUUCAUUUCUGGUUACUUAUGGUUUCUGUUGCCUGCCUUCAUUGUGUGAACCUUCUAGCUUCUGCCAUUGCUACUAAGUAAUAGUGACAGGUUCAGACUCAUGGUAGUGCUACAUUGACUGUAUUAGUAUUAGCCCAUAUAUAAUUGCAUGCUAUAUGGGUGUGCAUUUAGUGAUUUUUCUUGAUAAUUCUUAAUACUUACCUUUUUAAAUUCAUACUUAAUCUAAUUCCAUGAAAUGCAGCUUGCCUUCCACUUCAUGUUCCACUUCCAGAUCCAAACAAAGCAUGCCCACAAUUGUUGAUUGAUUGUGCUUUCUCUCAUUUACAUAAUCUUAAGAAGUGGAGUUGAUUGGUUAUCAUUUCAUUUAUCCUUGCUUGCUUCAAACUUUUCACACUGUUCUUAAGCCUUCAACCCCAUCUUUGCUUCCUUUAUAAAAGUCAGAUCUUGCUUAUAUCAUGACAAAAAGUAGAAGAUGUUUGUUUAUGCUCUUUUCACAUCAGGACUAUUUUUUAUCUUCUGUCUCUUCUUUGGAGGAAGAGCUGUUUUUCUGUUCCAAGUCCAGCACUUCCACCCUUGCCUGUCUACUUCACUGGACUUUCUUCCAACAACUCCUCCUCUUUACCCCUCCCCAGCUUCUGUCUCCCUGUCCACUAGCUCCUCUUCCUCAACCUACAAACAUGCUCAAAUUCCUUUCAGUCAAAAAAUAAACUUCUCUUCUAUACUACCUUGAACCUAGUUACUGCCAUCUAGUCUGUCAAACUUCCAUGUGCUCUCAUACUACCCUGUUUUAGUACUGAUUCUGUCACAUUGUAAUUGUUUAUUUCCUUGUUUUCCUUCUAUAUCAGACUGUAAGCUUCUGAGAAAUCUGUCUCUUGAUCCUGGUUGAUUCACCGAAGCCCAAGCUAGUUCCUAGUGCAUCGUACGCAUUCAGUAAAUAUUUUUUGAAUGAAUGAACAAUGUUAGAGCCAUGCCUCUGCCAUUCACUUUGUGAACUACCUGUAAUUUUUUUCUACCCCUACAUUUCGGUUGAAAGUUCACUUGAAGGUCACCACAUAAAUGUGAAAUCUAGUGGCUUCUCUCUUUACAUCAUGCUUGACCUCUGCAACCAUUAGUGCUUACAAAUUUACCUUUUCCACACAUUCAUGGUCACGUAUACCUGGGUCAUUUUGGGCCAGUCUCAGUAUUGCAUUCAAAAGAAGCAGACAAGCCCCGAACCUUUGGAAAGUAAUGAACUUCUGUAAUAUAUUAGUGAAAUCUUCUAAUGAGAUAGAAAUAUACAAUUACAUAAAGCUCAGCAAACUUCAAAUAAGUUCUUUUUACCCACCUUCCCAUAUCCUUACACAGCUUGGCACCUUCAAUCUCUCUUUUGUAACAGUUCACCCAAAACUUGUACACUUUUGGCCAAAAACCCCUUGUCCUUUGUCCCCUUUUUUCAUCUUCUAUGUUUAUUUUCUUCCAAGAAUAGAUUAUUCUUUCCAGUUUAAAUCACUUUAGCCUCUUUUGGCUCCUUCCAACCAAGUUCUUUCCUAAACCAGUUAUCUUACUCAGUAUUUUAGAAGUCCAGGAGCAUUGUCUUGAUUUCAUUUGGUUUGCCCUUACCAACUUUCUUUGCAUCAUUUUAUUUAAUCUUAAUGCCUCACAUCAGUGAGUAUUCCCUGACCUCCUGGGUGUCUCCCUUCUGUGUCUCUGUGGUGCCCCGUUUAUAACUCUCUGGAAAUAAUCUAUUUCUAUCUCUUCUCUAGGCUAUACAUUUCUUAAGGGUAGGAGUCCUGUCUUUUUUUUGUACCCCCAUAUCUAGCAUAGUACCUGGAACAUGGUGGGUGUUGAUAAAUGUUUAUUGGACUGAUGCUUCUGUGAAAUUUAAUACUUUCUCUUUUGCCACUGGCUUUUGUUUUGUUACUAGGUCUUCAAAUAUGGAUUAAGGUUUCCUUAAUGUCUUUUUUUCUUUUUAUAUACUCUUAGUGAUUCCUCUAUUCCCGAGGUAUCACUUAUCACUUCCAUAAAGAUGACUCCAGGUCCGUUUUCUAGUCUGGCUGUUCUCCUUAUUAUAAGACCAUUUGUUUUCAAAGUUGAAUGUCAGACAUCUCCACAUGAAUGUGUCACCAGUAUCUUAAAUGCAACAAAAAACUCAGUAAUCCAAACUUAUCUUCCUUUUAAAAUUUCUUCCUAUGUGCUCCAUGUCUCAGUUGUUCUAACCCCUACCCUUCCGGUUACCUAUGCUAGUUGGAAUCCUGGCAAAUGCCUUAACUUCUUUCUUUUAUACUCUCCCUAAUCUGUGAUCAAUGCCUAUCCAUCCUGCCUCUGAAUGUUUUUCACGUUUGCUUCCCCUUCCCAUCUCCACUUUUAGUAGUUUUGUUAUCACUUACCUUCACUAUUGCAGUAGUCUCUUAACUGACCUCUUUUCUAAUCUGUCUUCCGUGCUGUUGUUAGAAAUAUCUUCCUAAAACACAGAUCUGUUGUUACUGUAUGUUCAUCGCUUGACUAAUUUACUUAUCUUUCAGGUCUCUGCCAAAUGUCACUUCUAAAUAAAGUAUGUCUGUCUUCUUUGUUGUUUGUUUCAUGUUCCUUUCCUACUGUCAUCUAAUACUGUUUGUAAUUGUGUUUAUAUUUGUGCAUUGAUUUGUUUAAUGUCUUUCUUCCCACUGGAGAGAUUUAUGUAAGGGACUGGGGAGAGUUAUGUAGACCCUGGGCCUAGCACAAUGCUCGGGACAUAGUAACACUUAAAACAUAUCUGUUGAAUGAGUGGAUGGAUAAUAGCAAAGUACAGGCAGUGCAGGCAAACAGAUACCAAGUAGCAAAGGCAGGGAAAUUACAGGGUCCUAGACUCUUAGUACAUUCUCACAGACCUUAAUCUGUAGUUUAAAAUAGUAAUGGGCUUCUCUCUUUUGCUUUUUGCAUUUAUUUCCCUAAGGAUGAGAGUGAACAACUUACUACCCCACACUGACACUUCAGUGAGGGCACUGUGGAACCUUUCUAAUCAGAAGAUGGGACCAGGCUUGACAAUGAUUCAAUCAAAGCAGUUUUAGUGUCACACUUGUCUCAUGGAGGCUAUUUGUAUUUCUGAAGAAAUUCCAAUCAAAUAACAGCUUACUAGAUUUUUUUCCUGGUCUAAAUAUUAUUUUUGGGCAUUUUCCACAAAAAGCUUUUUGGGAAAGGUGGUUCUUACACUGGGGCUUGGAAUAAUUGUAUCUCUAUGCUUGGCCUUGGAAUAAUUCUGUCUCUGUUGGAAUUGUGCACACGUUGAGGCCUGAGGCCUUAUCUUUUAUAGGGCCUUCACUAUGUAGCUUCUCAUAUAUUCAGCAUCUUAGGAGAGAAUCAUAUUCAACAUAGUUUUGCUUUAAGCUUUUUACUUGGUAUCAGCAGUUUUGCCUUAAGUUCUAAAGCUUAAUAAUGAAACUCUGUUGAAUGAGAACCUUUCCAAAAGAUAUACUUUUCUACAUAAGCUGAGUUUAUUCAUCCAGAGUCAUCAAGAAUAGAUUAUAUUUAGAACAUAUGGAAUGAAUAAAUAUUAGUGAAUUCAUCUUUAUUGGACUUUUAAAUUUCUUUACAUAUAAUUCCAUUCACUCAUUUAUUCAGCCAUCUACACUUGAGCAACUACUUUAUGCCAAGGACUGUAGUAAACAUUUAGGAUCUGAAGAAAAAUAUGACUUGAUUACUCUUAAGAAUUUUAUAAGUCUAGGCUUUUUUUCAUGUCUGAGGCCAGAUUGAUUUUUCUUUUCCUUUUUUUCACUCAGGAUGAAGUACAUAGUGGUAUAAUCCUAGUUGACUGCAGCCUCGAACUCCUGGGCUCAGGUGAUUCUCCUUCCUCAGCUUCCUGAGUAGCUGGGAUACAAGCCUGUACCACCACACCUUGCUAAUUUUUAUUAUUUAUUUUCUGUAGAGAUGAGGUCUCUCUAUGUUGCUCAGGCUGGUGUCGAAUCCUGGCCUCAAGCAAUCCUCCUGACUUGGCUUCACAAAGCGAUGGGAUUACAGGCAUGCACCACCACACCUGGCCUUAGAGUGAUUUUUCUUAAGUGCAAAUUCGUGCUCUUUUUUCUAAGGCCUCAGCUUGGAAUGUCCUCUUGUAUUACCCACCUCUCUUCUUUCAGGACUCAUCUCUUAGGAACCUUCCCUGUCCAAGGCAGCUGAGUACCCUUCAGUAUACUCAUCCUACCCUCUCCCUCUCCUGUUGUGGCAGUUAGUACCAUGUUUUGUAACUACCUGUUUAUUUGGGUCUCCCCAACUAGACUGAAAAAGGCGCUUGAAGGCAGGGCUGUUUCCGUCCUUGUGUCCUGAGUGCUGAGCACAAUACUGAGUACAGUUUGUGACCUAUAGAAUUUGUGGAGGGAAGGCAUUUUGGAUGGAGGCUGUUGGUUAAGUGACCUGCAAAACUGCUCCAGUAUCAUGCCAGGAUCAGUCUUCUUUGCUCAUUAUUGAUGAGAAGCAACACUAACUUAUGUCUUUAUUCCUAACUUAAUUAUACUCCAAGUACACAUUUGCAUGCUUCAUUACAUGCCUGUAGUGAUAUCAGUGACACUGAUAAAGUAUUUUUUCAUAUUUUAGUUCUCAUGUUUUUGACUCUUUAUUUUAACUUUGUUGUUGAUUGAAUUGAGUAUUUGAGUUGCUGUUAGUAUAAAUAAAGUUUCCAUCUUGGAUGACUUACCAUGUUAACAAAAAAAAAAUCACAAGCAGUAUUAUGUGCUAGUGAUACCUUGUGAUUUAAAAUGUAUUUUGUUCCAGCAAAGAACCAGUUUGGGUCUCUUUGGAGAAUGGGCAUACAUCUGAGUUGACCUCAACUUUUCUGUAGGAGAGAUUAUUGAAUCUCCUAUAAAGGAUUAUAUGUAAAUAUAUAAAUUAACAUUUGUCUGUUUUACAAAAUAGAGUGUCUGAAACAAGAAUACAUAAAAUGUUAUUUUCAAUGUACUAGAGUAGAGGAGUUUGGUAUUUAAAGGAGUUCUGUACUUUGGUAAAGCCAAAAUUCCUUUGAUUACACUAGUGGUUGGUUAUUUAAUCAGGAUGUGAAUUCAAAUUGCCUACAAAAUUUUGAAAAAAUGCAGAUGUUUGGCUGACUCCACAUCUAUCAGAUUGCAAUUUCUAGUGGUAGUGUCCAAGCUCCUAUAUAUUUUGUACCAACUACCUGGGUAAUUUGAUGGGUUUUCAGAACUACUCAACUAUAUAAACCAAAGAACCUCAAACCUUAACAUAUAUAUGAUCAUGUGGGACCUUGUUAAAAUGCAGAUUCUGAGUCAGGAGCUCUGGGUGUGACCUGAGAUUUUCCAGUUCCAGCGAGCUCCAUGUGAUGUCCGUGCUGAUGGUGUGUGAUCCACACUUUGAACAAUAAGGCUAUAAAUAAUAACCAUCUACAUUUUAAAAGAUUUCCUUUUUUUUUUUCAUUUAAGUGUGGUGUAUCUGUUUCCUACUCUUGCUUAUUCUAUAAGAGAAGUGUAAUGGGCUUUAGAUCCAGUCUAAAAUAGUUUUGGUUUGGAUAUUGUCUUCCAUUAAAGUUUCAGUACGCAGAGGA